AUAACGCUACCUGCCGAGCAAGCCGAGUGGAGGGAGGCAAAGGCCAGGCUGAGGAUCAGGGUGGCCCGGGUGGCAGCGGGGAGGCGCUGCAUGCUGGAGGCUGUGCUGAGUGCCCGGUGCAGGUGAGCCGGUCCUGCGGAGUUGUGCCGAGUGCCUGCUGCAGUCUCAUUUCCAGUUCCUCCAUGACGUGGCAAGUGAAGACAGGAAUGAAAGGAAUGUAAAGCAGCUUUUCUCUGAAGAGAAGAAGAGAGAGAGACACAGCCAAGACCGAGGCUGGGCCAAGAUGGUGUCUGUGUUUCGAAGCGAGGAGAUGUGUUUGUCACAACUGUUUCUCCAGGUGGAAGCUGCAUAUUGCUGUGUGGCUGAGCUCGGAGAGCUCGGAUUGGUUCAGUUCAAAGAUUUAAAUAUGAAUGUGAACAGCUUUCAAAGGAAAUUUGUGAAUGAAGUCAGAAGGUGUGAAUCACUGGAGAGAAUCCUCCGUUUUCUGGAAGACGAGAUGCAAAAUGAGAUUGUAGUUCAGUUGCUCGAGAAAAGCCCACUGACCCCGCUCCCACGGGAAAUGAUUACCCUGGAGACUGUUCUAGAAAAACUGGAAGGAGAGUUACAGGAAGCCAACCAGAACCAGCAGGCCUUGAAACAAAGCUUCCUAGAACUGACAGAACUGAAAUACCUCCUGAAGAAAACCCAAGACUUCUUUGAGACGGAAACCAAUUUAGCUGAUGAUUUCUUUACUGAGGACACUUCUGGCCUCCUGGAGUUGAAAGCAGUGCCUGCAUAUAUGACCGGAAAGUUGGGGUUCAUAGCCGGUGUGAUCAACAGGGAGAGGAUGGCUUCCUUUGAGCGGUUACUGUGGCGAAUCUGCCGAGGAAACGUGUACUUGAAGUUCAGUGAGAUGGACGCCCCUCUGGAGGAUCCUGUGACGAAAGAAGAAAUUCAGAAGAACAUAUUCAUCAUAUUUUACCAAGGAGAGCAGCUCAGGCAGAAAAUCAAGAAGAUCUGUGAUGGGUUUCGAGCCACUGUCUACCCUUGCCCAGAGCCUGCGGUGGAGCGCAGAGAGAUGUUGGAGAGCGUCAAUGUGAGGCUGGAAGAUUUAAUCACCGUCAUAACACAAACAGAGUCUCACCGCCAGCGCCUGCUGCAGGAAGCCGCUGCCAACUGGCACUCCUGGCUCAUCAAGGUGCAGAAGAUGAAAGCUGUCUACCACAUCCUGAACAUGUGCAACAUCGACGUCACCCAGCAGUGUGUCAUCGCCGAGAUCUGGUUCCCGGUGGCAGAUGCCACACGUAUCAAGAGGGCACUGGAGCAAGGCAUGGAACUAAGUGGCUCCUCCAUGGCCCCCAUCAUGACCACAGUGCAAUCUAAAACAGCCCCUCCCACAUUUAACAGGACCAAUAAAUUCACAGCUGGCUUCCAGAAUAUUGUUGAUGCCUAUGGUGUCGGCAGCUACCGGGAGAUAAACCCAGCCCCCUACACCAUCAUCACUUUCCCCUUCCUGUUCGCUGUGAUGUUUGGAGACUGUGGUCAUGGAACCGUGAUGCUCCUGGCUGCACUUUGGAUGAUUCUGAAUGAGAGACGCUUGCUCUCCCAGAAGACAGACAAUGAGAUUUGGAACACCUUCUUCCACGGGCGCUAUCUGAUCCUACUUAUGGGCAUCUUCUCCAUCUACACGGGUUUGAUCUACAAUGACUGCUUCUCCAAGUCCUUGAACAUCUUUGGCUCUUCUUGGAGUGUCCAACCCAUGUUCAGAAACGGCACAUGGAAUACUCAUGUAAUGGAGGAAAGUCUAUAUCUGCAGCUGGACCCAGCCAUACCAGGAGUGUAUUUUGGAAAUCCAUACCCGUUUGGGAUUGAUCCGAUUUGGAACUUGGCUUCAAACAAACUCACAUUUCUGAACUCGUAUAAAAUGAAGAUGUCGGUGAUCCUGGGAAUUGUCCAGAUGGUUUUCGGUGUCAUCCUCAGCCUUUUCAAUCACAUAUACUUCAGAAGAACUCUCAACAUCAUUCUGCAAUUUAUCCCUGAGAUGAUUUUUAUCCUGUGUCUGUUUGGAUACCUGGUUUUCAUGAUCAUUUUCAAAUGGUGCUGCUUUGACGUCCAUGUAUCUCAGCACGCCCCCAGCAUCCUCAUCCACUUCAUCAACAUGUUUCUGUUUAACUACAGUGACUCUUCCAACGCACCCCUCUACAAACAUCAGCAAGAAGUCCAAAGUUUCUUUGUGGUUAUGGCUUUGAUUUCUGUGCCGUGGAUGCUUCUGAUUAAGCCGUUUAUUCUUAGAGCCAGUCAUCGGAAAUCCCAGCUGCAGGCAUCCAGGAUCCAAGAAGAUGCCACUGAGAACAUUGAAGGUGAUAGCUCCAGCCCUUCUAGCCGUUCUGGCCAGAGGACUUCUGCAGAUACCCACGGGGCUCUGGACGACCAUGGAGAAGAGUUCAACUUUGGAGACGUCUUUGUCCACCAAGCCAUCCACACCAUCGAGUACUGCCUGGGCUGCAUUUCAAACACAGCCUCCUACCUGCGGCUCUGGGCCCUCAGCCUGGCUCAUGCACAACUGUCUGAAGUGCUCUGGACUAUGGUGAUGAACAGCGGCCUUCAGACGCGAGGCUGGGGAGGAAUCGUCGGGGUUUUUAUUAUUUUUGCCGUAUUUGCUGUCCUGACAGUAGCCAUCCUUCUGAUCAUGGAGGGCCUCUCUGCUUUCCUGCACGCCCUGCGACUGCACUGGGUUGAGUUCCAGAACAAGUUCUAUGUCGGGGAUGGUUACAAGUUUUCUCCAUUCUCCUUUAAACACAUCCUGGAUGGCACAGCCGAGGAGUAGGCUGAGGGCUGCACCUCCCACGGUGGUCACCAUGCCAAUGAAGGAAGUUCAGUCUUGUCUUUGAUAUCAGCCCCUGCAAGGCGCUCAAUGGGAAGGUUGUUCUUGGCUCACCUGAAGCAUGAAACUGUGUAUUAUUUGGACGUCAGCCUGUGGAUUUGAUACGACUUAACCACGUCAGAGGAAGGACUUUGGCAAGUGAUAUUGUCUUCAUGUGGGGUAUUAAUUCUCAAAUAAUAAAGUAAUUGACAAAUGAGGGGAGAAUGCUAAACAGAUGUCUUCUUGCAAUAUUUUAAAUAUUGUAUUUGAGAAAAUAAACAUCUGAGUCAUUCA